ACAGCCGAGCCGCGCCGGGCCCCUGGACGGCGUCGCCAAGGAGCUGGGAUCGCACUUGCUGCAGGUUCCACCCAGCGCUUGCUCUGUGCCAGGCGCCAGGGCUGGAGCAGCAGAAAUGAUUGGGCUGCUCUGAGCUCUGAAGCAUUCGGCCGCUGUGUGUGUGCAAGGGGCGCAAGGACGGAGAGACAGCAUCAAUAAUACAAUAUUAACAGGAGCACUUGUCCAGAGCUUACUGCAAGCCACAUUCAGUUCCGGACCUUAUUGACUUCCCCCUCCCAUCUAGAGUGGAUUCUGGUUUUUCAAUUUGUUUUGUUUUGUUUUUUGUUUGUUUGUUUGUUUUUGAGACGGAGUCUCACUCUGUGGCCCAGGCUAGAGUGCAAUGGCGCGAUCUCGGCUCACUCCAACCUCCGCCUCCCGGGUUCAAGCGAUUCUCCCGCUUCAGCCUCCCGAGUAGCCAGGAUUGCAGGCACCCGCCAUCAUGCCUGGCUAAUUUUUGUAGAGACAGGGUUUCACCCAGGCUGGUCUCGAUCUCCUGACCUCCGAUGAUCCGCCCACCUCAGCCUUCCAAAGUGUUGGGAUUACAGGCGUGAGCCAACGCGUCCUGCCUUGAUUCUGUUUUUAACUCCAUUUUUUAGAGGAGGAAAUUGAGGCACAGAGAGGUUAAAUAACAUGUCUAAGGUCACACAGCAAGGGGUGGAGCGGAGUUAGCCCACUGGCCUAGCUCUAGAGCCCACCCGGAUAACCAGAACUUGGUGAGGCCUCCGGGCUCUUGCUUGGUUUGGAGCCAGGUGCUUAGCGCCCCGAGCCCGGGGCCAUUCACCCUGCAGGAGCUGCACGCGCCCCUGACCUCGGCUUUUCCCUGGCAGCAGAGGGGCUUUGCGGGUCGGCCGGGUAGCCCUGAGCACAGCUCGCCACUUCCAGGUGGGCUGUUGGCGCUGGCUGGGGACACAUCCCGAUCUUUCAAAUGCCCUUUACAGAGCCUCAUCAACGACCCGAUUCAUUCCCCCCUCCUGUCAUUUGUCUCUGCCAUCGAAAAAUGCCUACCGAGAGCUGCUCUGCAUUUCCGCCCUCUAUUUUGUGUUUUACUUUAAAAUAAUAAUAAAAAAAAUGUUGGCUGCAGGACGCCAUGACUUAGGUCAGCGAGUCAGCCGCUAGCUCUGCAUUUCCAAAAAGCAGAUCUUUUCACAACUCUCUUGCCCCAAGUGCCCUGGUGUGGUUUAUUUUUUAAAAUGCAUGCCUGCGGAAGAGAAGACCCGGGGAAUAUUCGAAACCCCGAGCUUUUACAACAUAAAGCGCAUGGUGUGGCCGCGGCGAGUAAUGGCGCUCUGGGAGCCCUGCCCAGGCGGCCUCUGCUCGCCCUCCUCCACUUCCAGCUCCGAGCUGGGUGUGUUGCAAGUUUCAUACUCCUACAUAUUAUAAGUGACACUAAUAUCAGGGACAACUAAGUGCUGGGGAACUUCAAUGAAAACCUGGCUGGUAAAGUCAACACCCCCAGACUUCUCUGUGCUACAUUUCUUUAAUUAAUUCCGGAGUGGUGUGUGGACGGGCGUCUUUGCAGUUAUUAUACACGUAAGUGAAUUAGGCCAUUUGAAGCUACGAAGUCAUACCCAACAUUUUCCAUUAAGAAUAUUAUUUUUUUAGCUACUGCUGGCAACUUUUAGAAUUUAAUUAUGAUAAUUUUCCUCUUUUCCUCAUUAUCCCAGAUAUGGCUGGUUGUGAGAUACUUUUUCACUAAAUGUGUCUCUUUAAUGAUUUUGGAAUUAAGCAAGCAUGCCAAAUGCGCCAAGACAUUUAUAACUUUAGAAAUUGCUGUAUAGUAUAUAUUUUUGGAACACCACAGGUUUAGUUGGGAAAAUAUUUUGCAGCUGAGUUAGAAACUUGAAAGUUAGGCUUAUAAUCAAGAUGCUGAUUUUCAACCUUAGCAUCGGGGAAGGUAAUGAUAGUUUAGUUGGCAAAGACUUUUUGCAGCAAACUGUAUUUGAGACAGCAGAAUCCAAGGAUAUCUUUCAAGAUUCACUUAUACUACAUUCUUUUUAGCCCCCUCUCUAGGGGUGGAGGGGGUGGCUUAGAAAAACCAAAGGUAAUCUGGUUUCAAUUACAUGCUGUAAAAAUAGAAUUUGUGGCCAGAAAUUAAUUUGGAAUAUUUUUUAUGGGGGCAACAUUGUGGGUUGUAUGAGUCUUUCACCAACUUUAUUGCUUUUCUUUGGUUCUGGAUCUAAAAUAUGAAUGAGUAAAUAAAAUACAGUUUCCUUUUUCAAAAAUAAUUUAGUCUUUUUAUCCUUGACACAUAAAUAUAAUCAUUACCUUUUUAUUUGUCUUAAUUACCUCUUAUAGUUUUACUUUAUUUUUGAGGGUUAGCCAACUUAGGAAAAAUCAGAAUUUCAUUUGGGUAGUUUUCAUUUUUCAGAAGUUGAUACUUUUCCUCCUUGAAUUUUGCAAAGGUUAUUUGAUCUCUUGCAAAUUCUAAAUAAUUAAUUCUGUAGACAUAGUCUGGUAAAAUAACCAGGUAUUUUGUUUUAUUUUCUGGGCAGUGGUAGUGUUCGGAAUUUAUUAUUCCAACGGUACUUAGAGGUAACUAGAAAAUUGUGGCAAAUAAAGCAUAUGUCCUAGUGGUAUAAAUGACUGCCAAUUAUGACAUAAAAUGGUCUAUAUAGUGGUAGAUUUUCCCCUAAGUACCAUAGAACUCCGGAUUUGUACUAAGUGCUAAAAUAACCCCAAACAAUAAAGCUACUACGUUUAACCUGAGCUUGAUAGGAAUUCUCAAAUGUUUUGCAUGAUUUUUGUGAUGUGGAUGUAUGAUUGUUUCUAAAGUGCUUUAAAAGCAUUUCAGAGCCUGGCCUGGGAACUAAACCCUGGGUGCUGUUUCCUACAGUCCUUUUUAAGACCCUGGGCUUCAUUUUUGCAUUUAGCAAGUAUGUGUUGAUGGUCAUAUUUGAUGCAUCCCUCCAUCCCAGUGACUGUACCAUUGUUAGAUUUAACUCUAAUGUAGAAUGAUCAUCUCUUAUUCUGACACUUUAUCUUUUACAGACUUUGGAUGGAUUUGUUUUUGUGGUAGCAUCUGAUGGCAAAAUCAUGUAUAUAUCCGAGACCGCUUCUGUCCAUUUAGGCUUAUCCCAGGUGGAGCUCACGGGCAACAGUAUUUAUGAAUACAUCCAUCCUUCUGACCACGAUGAGAUGACCGCUGUCCUCACGGCCCACCAGCCGCUGCACCACCACCUGCUCCAAGAGUAUGAGAUAGAGAGGUCGUUCUUUCUUCGAAUGAAAUGUGUCUUGGCGAAAAGGAACGCGGGCCUGACCUGCAGCGGAUACAAGGUCAUCCACUGCAGUGGCUACUUGAAGAUCAGGCAGUAUAUGCUGGACAUGUCCCUGUACGACUCCUGCUACCAGAUUGUGGGGCUGGUGGCCGUGGGCCAGUCGCUGCCACCCAGUGCCAUCACCGAGAUCAAGCUGUACAGUAACAUGUUCAUGUUCAGGGCCAGCCUUGACCUGAAGCUGAUAUUCCUGGAUUCCAGGGUGACCGAGGUGACGGGGUACGAGCCGCAGGACCUGAUCGAGAAGACCCUAUACCAUCACGUGCACGGCUGCGACGUGUUCCACCUCCGCUACGCACACCACCUCCUGUUGGUGAAGGGCCAGGUCACCACCAAGUACUACCGGCUGCUGUCCAAGCGGGGCGGCUGGGUGUGGGUGCAGAGCUACGCCACCGUGGUGCACAACAGCCGCUCGUCCCGGCCCCACUGCAUCGUGAGUGUCAAUUAUGUACUCACGGAGAUUGAAUACAAGGAACUUCAGCUGUCCCUGGAGCAGGUGUCCACUGCCAAGUCCCAGGACUCCUGGAGGACCGCCUUGUCUACCUCACAAGAAACUAGGAAAUUAGUGAAACCCAAAAAUACCAAGAUGAAGACAAAGCUGAGAACAAACCCUUACCCCCCACAGCAAUACAGCUCGUUCCAAAUGGACAAACUGGAAUGCGGCCAGCUCGGAAACUGGAGAGCCAGUCCCCCUGCAAGCGCUGCUGCUCCUCCAGAACUGCAGCCCCACUCAGAAAGCAGUGACCUUCUGUACACGCCAUCCUACAGCCUGCCCUUCUCCUACCAUUACGGACACUUCCCUCUGGACUCUCACGUCUUCAGCAGCAAAAAGCCAAUGUUGCCGGCCAAGUUCGGGCAGCCCCAAGGAUCCCCUUGUGAGGUGGCACGCUUUUUCCUGAGCACACUGCCAGCCAGCGGUGAAUGCCAGUGGCAUUAUGCCAACCCCCUAGUGCCUAGCAGCUCGUCUCCAGCUAAAAAUCCUCCAGAGCCACCGGCGAACACUGCUAGGCACAGCCUGGUGCCAAGCUACGAAGCGCCCGCCGCCGCCGUGCGCAGGUUCGGCGAGGACACCGCGCCCCCGAGCUUCCCGAGCUGCGGCCACUACCGCGAGGAGCCCGCGCUGGGCCCGGCCAAAGCCGCCCGCCAGGCCGCCCGGGACGGGGCGCGGCUGGCGCUGGCCCGCGCGGCACCCGAGUGCUGCGCGCCCCCGACCCCCGAGGCCCCGGGCGCGCCGGCGCAGCUGCCCUUCGUGCUGCUCAACUACCACCGCGUGCUGGCCCGGCGCGGACCGCUGGGGGGCGCCGCACCCGCCGCCUCCGGCCUGGCCUGCGCUCCCGGCGGCCCCGAGGCGGCGACCGGCGCGCUGCGGCUCCGGCACCCGAGCCCCGCCGCCACCUCCCCGCCCGGCGCGCCCCUGCCGCACUACCUGGGCGCCUCGGUCAUCAUCACCAACGGGAGGUGACCCGCUGGCCGCCCGCGCCAGGAGCCUGGACCCGGCCUCCCGGGGCUGCGGCGCCACCGAGCCCGGCAAAUGCGCACGACCUACAUUAAUUUAUGCAGAGACAGCUGUUUGAAUUGGACCCCGCCGCCGACUUGCGGAUUUCCACCGCGGAGGCCCCGCGCGCCGGUGCCGAGGGCCGAGGAGCGCCCGGGUCCGGGCAGGUGACCGCCCGCCUCUGUCCUGCGAGGGCCGGUGCGACCCAGUUGCUGGGGGCUUGGUUUCCUCACCUUGAAAUCGGGCUUCACGCGUCUUGCCUUGUCCCCAACGUUCCACAACAGUCCCGCUGGGGGAUUGAAGCGGUUUCACUCCGCAAAUAUCCUCCACUUUCAGGAGGGAAAACCCACCCUACCACAGUCCGCUCUUCCAAGUGGACGGCAGACCUGGGAGGGGACGCCUGUGUCACGAGCCCUUUUAGAUGCUUAGGUGAAGGCAGAAGUGAUGAUUGUAAGUCCCAUGAAUACACAACUCCACUGUCUUUAAAAGUCAUUCAAGAGUCUCAUUAUUUUUGUUUUUAUUUAACCCUUUCUUCAAUACAAAAAGCCAACAAACCAAGACUAAGGGGGUGACCAUGCAAUUCCAUUUUGUGUCUGUGAACAUAGGUGUGCUUCCCAAAUACAUUAACAAGCUCUUACUUCCCCCUAACCCCUAUGAACUCUUGAUAACACCAAGAGUAGCACCUUCAGAAUAUAUUGAAUAGGCAUUAAAUGCAAAAAUAUAUAUGUAGCCAGACAGUUUAUGAGAAUGACCCUGUCAAGCUUCAUUAUUACGUGGCAAAAUCCCUCUGGCCCACACAGAUCUGUAAUUCACUAGGCUCGUGUUUGCUACAAAUAGUGCUAAUAAAGUUAAAUUGCACGUGCAAUACGGAACACUGUCAAUGGACUGCACCUUGUGAAGGAAAAACAUGCUUAAGGGGGUGUAAUGAAAAUGAUGUAGACAUUUUAAGCAUUUUCUACACAGCGAGAAAACUUCGUAAGAACAUGUUACGUGUGCAACAGGUAAACAGAAAUCCUUUCAUAAAGCACCAGCAGUGUUUAAAAAAUGAGCUUCCAUUAAUUUUUACUUUUUAUGGGUUUUGCUUAAAGAUCUCAACAUGGAAAAAUCCUGUCAUGGCUCUGAACUGCACAAUGCAUUGAACCGCCGUCCUUCAAUUUUCUUCACACUAUCAACACUGCAGCAUUUUGCUGCUUUAUCAAAAUGGUUUAUUUUAGGAAACUUUUUCCACCUUUCUGAAUGGAAAGAGGUUUUCACAAAUGUUUUAAACUCAUCGUUCUAAAAUCAAGUGCACCUACACCAACUGCUCUCAAAAUGUGAACUGACUUUUUUUUUUUUUUUUUUGCCAACCCUGUGUCACUUAGUGAGGACCUGACACAAUCCCUACAGGGUGUCUGUCAGUGGGCCUCAUGGUAAGAGUCACAAUUUGCAAAUUUAGGACCGUGGGUCAUGCAGCGAAGGGGCUGGAUGGUAGGAAGGGAUGUGCCCGCCUCUCCACGCACUCAGCUAUACCUCAUUCACAGCUCCUUGUGAGUGUGUGCACAGGAAAUAAGCCGAGGGUAUUAUUUUUUUAUGUUCAUGAGUCUUGUAAUUAAACCGUGAUUCUUGAAAGGUGUAGGUUUGAUUACUAGGAGAUACCACCGACAUUUUUCAAUAAAGUACUGCAAAAUGCUUUUGUGUCUACCUUGUUAUUAACUUUUGGGGCUGUAUUUAGUAAAAAUAAAUCAAGGCUAUCGGAGCAGUUCAAUAACAAAGGUUACUGUUGAGAAAAAAGACCCUAUCAUAGAUUUACAAG